GCCCGCCUCCUGCGCCGCCCCUUCCGAGGCUAAAUCGGCUGCGUUCCUCUCGGAACGCGCCGCAGAAGGGGUCCUGGUGACGAGUCCCGCGUUCUCUCCUUGAAUCCACUCGCCAGCCCGCCGCCCUCUGCCGCCGCACCCUGCACACCCGCCCCUCUCCUGUGCCAGGCAAGGUGACCCCAUGGCAAGGCGCAAGCCAGAAGGGUCCAGCUUCAACAUGACCCACCUGUCCAUGGCUAUGGCCUUUUCCUUUCCCCCAGUUGCCAGUGGGCAACUCCACCCUCAGCUGGGCAACACCCAGCACCAGACAGAGUUAGGAAAGGAACUUGCUACUACCAGCACCAUGCCCUACCAAUAUCCAGCACUGACCCCGGAGCAGAAGAAGGAGCUGUCUGACAUCGCUCACCGCAUCGUGGCACCUGGCAAGGGCAUCCUGGCUGCAGAUGAGUCCACUGGGAGCAUUGCCAAGCGGCUGCAGUCCAUUGGCACCGAGAACACCGAGGAGAACCGGCGCUUCUACCGCCAGCUGCUGCUGACAGCUGACGACCGCGUGAACCCCUGCAUUGGGGGUGUCAUCCUCUUCCAUGAGACACUCUACCAGAAGGCGGAUGAUGGGCGUCCCUUCCCCCAAGUUAUCAAAUCCAAGGGCGGUGUUGUGGGCAUCAAGGUAGACAAGGGCGUGGUCCCCCUGGCAGGGACAAAUGGCGAGACUACCACCCAAGGGUUGGAUGGGCUGUCUGAGCGCUGUGCCCAGUACAAGAAGGACGGAGCUGACUUCGCCAAGUGGCGUUGUGUGCUGAAGAUUGGGGAACACACCCCCUCAGCCCUCGCCAUCAUGGAAAAUGCCAAUGUUCUGGCCCGUUAUGCCAGUAUCUGCCAGCAGAAUGGCAUUGUGCCCAUCGUGGAGCCUGAGAUCCUCCCUGAUGGGGACCAUGACUUGAAGCGCUGCCAGUAUGUGACCGAGAAGGUGCUGGCUGCUGUCUACAAGGCUCUGAGUGACCACCACAUCUACCUGGAAGGCACCUUGCUGAAGCCCAACAUGGUCACCCCAGGCCAUGCUUGCACUCAGAAGUUUUCUCAUGAGGAGAUUGCCAUGGCGACCGUCACAGCGCUGCGCCGCACAGUGCCCCCCGCUGUCACUGGGAUCACCUUCCUGUCUGGAGGCCAGAGUGAGGAGGAGGCGUCCAUCAACCUCAAUGCCAUUAACAAGUGCCCCCUGCUGAAGCCCUGGGCCCUGACCUUCUCCUACGGCCGAGCCCUGCAGGCCUCUGCCCUGAAGGCCUGGGGCGGGAAGAAGGAGAACCUGAAGGCUGCGCAGGAGGAGUAUGUCAAGCGAGCCCUGGCCAACAGCCUUGCCUGUCAAGGAAAGUACACUCCGAGCGGUCAGGCUGGGGCUGCUGCCAGCGAGUCCCUCUUCGUCUCUAACCACGCCUAUUAAGCGGAGGUGUUCCCAGGCUGCCCCCAACACUCCAGGCCCUGCCCCCUCCCACUCUUGAAGAGGAGGCCGCCUCCUCGGGGCUCCAGGCUGGCUUGCCCGCGCUCUUUCUUCCCUCGUGACAGUGGUGUGUGGUGUCGUCUGUGAAUGCUAAGUCCAUCACCCUUUCCGGCACACUGCCAAAUAAACAGCUAUUUAAGGGGGA